GCCAGGAGCCACCGUCCGAGCCUUGCGGAGCGCGGCAGUGGGCGCCGGCUGCCCGCAGCCCCUGACCCGGCCCCGGACGGAGCGCCGGCCGCACCACCGCCCUCUGGCCGUUGCCUCACCGGCUCGGCAAGAUGUCGGUGAAGGAGGGCGCACAGCGCAAGUGGGCAGCGCUGAAGGAGAAGCUGGGGCCACAGGAUUCGGACCCCACGGAGGCCAACCUGGAGAGCGCGGACCCCGAGCUGUGCAUCCGGCUGCUCCAGAUGCCCUCUGUGGUCAACUACUCCGGCCUGCGCAAGCGCCUGGAGGGCAGCGACGGCGGCUGGAUGGUGCAGUUCCUGGAGCAGAGCGGCCUGGACCUGCUGCUGGAGGCGCUGGCGCGGCUGUCGGGCCGCGGCGUUGCACGUAUCUCCGACGCCCUGCUGCAGCUCACCUGCGUCAGCUGCGUGCGCGCCGUCAUGAACUCGCGGCAGGGCAUCGAGUACAUCCUCAGCAACCAGGGCUACGUGCGCCAGCUCUCCCAGGCCCUGGACACAUCCAACGUGAUGGUGAAGAAGCAGGUGUUUGAGCUACUGGCUGCCCUGUGCAUCUACUCUCCCGAGGGCCACGUGCUGACCCUGGACGCCCUGGACCACUACAAGACGGUGUGCAGCCAGCAGUACCGCUUCAGCAUUGUCAUGAACGAGCUCUCCGGCAGCGACAACGUGCCCUACGUGGUCACCCUGCUUAGCGUGAUCAACGCCGUCAUCUUGGGCCCCGAGGACCUGCGCGCGCGCACCCAGCUGCGGAACGAGUUUAUCGGGCUGCAGCUGCUGGACGUCCUGGCUCGCCUGCGAGACCUGGAGGAUGCCGACCUGCUGAUCCAGCUGGAGGCUUUCGAGGAGGCUAAGGCCGAGGACGAGGAGGAGCUGCUGCGAGUCUCUGGCGGGGUCGACAUGAGCAGCCACCAGGAGGUCUUUGCCUCCCUGUUCCACAAGGUGAGCUGCUCCCCGGUGUCUGCCCAGCUCCUGUCGGUGCUGCAGGGCCUCCUGCACCUGGAGCCCACCCUCCGCUCCAGCCAGCUGCUCUGGGAGGCCCUGGAGAGCCUCGUGAACCGGGCCGUGCUCCUGGCCAGCGAUGCCCAGGAAUGCACCCUGGAGGAAGUGGUUGAGCGGCUCCUGUCUGUCAAGGGGCGACCCAGACCGAGCCCCCUGGUCAAGGCCCAUAAAAGCGUCCAGGCCAACCUAGACCAGAGCCAGAGGGGCAGCUCCCCGCAAAACACUACAACCCCCAAGCCCAGCGUGGAGGGCCAGCAGCCAGCAGCAGCUGCUGCCUGCGAGCCCGUGGACCACGCCCAGAGUGAGAGCAUCCUGAAAGUUUCGCAGCCCAGAGCCCUGGAGCAGCAGGCGUCCACCCCACCCCCACCCCCACCCCCACCCCUGCUCCCUGGUUCCAGUGCCGAGCCCCCUCCCCCUCCCCCACCACCCCCCCUGCCCAGUGUGGGGGCUAAGGCCCUCCCAACAGCACCCCCGCCCCCACCCCUGCCAGGCCUGGGGGCCAUGGCCCCCCCAGCACCUCCUCUACCACCACCCCUGCCAGGCUCCUGUGAGUUCCUGCCCCCACCACCUCCACCACUCCCGGGCUUGGGAUGCCCGCCCCCACCCCCACCCCUGCUGCCUGGUAUGGGCUGGGGCCCUCCUCCACCCCCACCUCCACUACUGCCCUGCACCUGCAGCCCCCCCGUGGCGGGAGGCAUGGAGGAGGUCAUCGUGGCCCAGGUGGACCAUGGCUUGGGCUCAGCAUGGGUCCCCAGCCAUCGGCGGGUGAACCCACCCACACUGCGCAUGAAGAAGCUGAACUGGCAGAAGCUGCCAUCCAACGUGGCACGUGAGCACAACUCUAUGUGGGCGUCCCUGAGCAGCCCCGACGCCGAGGCUGUGGAGCCCGACUUCUCCAGCAUCGAGCGACUAUUCUCCUUCCCUGCAGCCAAGCCCAAGGAGCCCACCAUGGUGGCCCCCCGGGCCAGGAAGGAGCCCAAGGAGAUCACUUUCCUCGAUGCCAAGAAGAGCCUGAACCUCAACAUCUUCCUGAAGCAAUUUAAGUGCUCCAACGAGGAGGUCGCUGCUAUGAUCCGGGCUGGAGAUACCACCAAGUUUGAUGUGGAGGUUCUCAAACAACUCCUUAAGCUCCUUCCCGAGAAGCACGAGAUUGAAAACCUGCGGGCAUUCACAGAGGAGCGAGCCAAGCUGGCCAGCGCCGACCACUUCUACCUCCUCCUGCUGGCCAUUCCCUGCUACCAGCUGCGAAUCGAGUGCAUGCUGCUGUGUGAGGGCGCGGCCGCCGUGCUGGACAUGGUGCGGCCCAAGGCCCAGCUGGUGCUGGCUGCCUGCGAAAGCCUGCUCACCAGCCGCCAGCUGCCCAUCUUCUGCCAGCUGAUCCUGAGAAUUGGGAACUUCCUCAACUACGGCAGCCACACCGGUGACGCCGACGGCUUCAAGAUCAGCACAUUGCUGAAGCUCACGGAGACCAAGUCCCAGCAGAACCGCGUGACGCUGCUGCACCACGUGCUGGAGGAAGCGGAAAAGAGCCACCCCGACCUCCUGCAGCUGCCCCGGGACCUGGAACAGCCCUCGCAAGCAGCAGGGAUCAACCUGGAGAUCAUCCGCUCAGAGGCCAGCUCCAACCUGAAGAAGCUUCUGGAGACCGAGCGGAAGGUGUCUGCCUCCGUGGCCGAGGUCCAGGAGCAGUACACCGAGCGCCUCCAGGCCAGCAUCUCGGCCUUCCGGGCACUGGAUGAGCUGUUUGAGGCCAUCGAGCAGAAGCAACGGGAGCUGGCCGACUACCUGUGUGAGGACGCCCAGCAGCUGUCCCUGGAGGACACGUUCAGCACCAUGAAGGCUUUCCGGGACCUUUUCCUCCGCGCCCUGAAGGAGAACAAGGACCGGAAGGAGCAGGCGGCGAAGGCAGAGAGGAGGAAGCAGCAGCUGGCGGAGGAGGAGGCGCGGCGGCCUCGGGGAGAGGACGGGAAGCCUGUCAGGAAGGGGCCCGGGAAGCAGGAGGAGGUGUGUGUCAUCGAUGCCCUGCUGGCUGACAUCAGGAAGGGCUUCCAGCUGCGGAAGACAGCCCGGGGCCGCGGGGACACCGACGGGGGCAGCAAGGCAGCCUCCAUGGAUCCCCCAAGAGCCACAGAGCCUGUGGCCACCAGUAACCCUGCAGGAGAUCCCGUGGGCAGCACGCGCUGUCCCGCCUCUGAGCCCGGCCUUGAUGCUACAACAGCCAGCGAGUCCCGGGGCUGGGACCUUGUAGACGCCGUGACCCCCGGCCCUCAGCCCACCCUGGAGCAGUUGGAGGAGGGUGGUCCACGGCCCCUGGAGAGGCGUUCUUCCUGGUAUGUGGAUGCCAGCGAUGUCCUAACCACUGAGGAUCCCCAGUGCCCCCAGCCCUUGGAGGGGGCCUGGCCGGUGACUCUGGGAGAUGCUCAGGCCCUGAAGCCCCUCAAGUUCUCCAGCAACCAGCCCCCUGCAGCCGGAAGUUCAAGGCAAGAUGCCAAGGAUCCCACGUCCUUGCUGGGCGUCCUCCAGGCCGAGGCCGACAGCACAAGUGAGGGGCUGGAGGACGCUGUCCACAGCCGUGGUGCCAGACCCCCUGCAGCAGGCCCAGGUGGGGAUGAGGACGAGGACGAGGAGGACACGGCCCCAGAGUCCGCACUGGACACAUCCCUGGACAAGUCCUUCUCCGAGGAUGCGGUGACCGACUCCUCGGGGUCGGGCACACUCCCCAGGGCCCGGGGCCGGGCCUCAAAGGGGACCGGGAAGCGAAGGAAGAAGCGUCCCUCCAGGAGCCAGGAAGAGGUUCCCCCUGAUUCUGAUGAUAAUAAAACAAAGAAACUGUGUGUGAUCCAGUAAGGCCUCAGGCCCAGGCCCAAGGCCAAGUGAGAGAGCCCAGGCCACAGGACAUGCUGCCAUUCUGCCAAGAGAGGCUCUUCUGGGGGCCAGGCUGGGACUGGGCCCCGGAAACCAAAACUCCGUGCCUUACCCAGCCGGGGCCCUCCUGGAGCCUUCUUGGGGUGUUGUGGCUGGGAACCCGACAGGCACCAGUGCCCUGCCAGGCCUGGUGCCCUCCUGGACCGCCUGCACGUGCCAGCCUCCCACCUGCUUCCUAAAGGCAACCCUGGCCCACACCCGCAUGCGCCCGGUGCAGCCUGCCAAGGGCCAGUCGGGGGGUGCUGCGUCCUGCCAGUGUCCACCACAGCUCUGCCUGCCCUUCAGCCCAGCAAGGUUUAAUCAAAAUGCAAUGCUUUGCAAGUCUUUACUGCUUGGAGGUGGCUGAGUUGGGGGCCCUGGGCAGGGGUAAGCUGGCAGGCAGUGCCAUGGCAGGCCAGGGUCCCCUCCCAUGGGGUCUGGCCCCCGUUCCAGCAUGUCCAGCCCCUGAAGUUGGAGUGGGGGGCGGUCUGCCUUUGCUGCCACUGCCAGGCCUCUGCCCUGCAGCUGAAACUUGGCCAUCACAUCAACAGAAAACCCCUCCCAGUGCCAGCUGCCCAGCGUGGGCAGGCCCUGGGGACAAUACAGGUCCACCUGAGGGGCUGCAGGGUGACACCCAGCAGCCGCUGCCCCCUCACUGCCCACCCAGCGAGGGCAGCCUACCCGAGCCUGCCCCCUGCCAGGUGUGUGCCCUGAGGCUGGCGGCUGGAUGCGUGGCCAAUAAAAAGCAGACCUAGCCCGGUGUGCGACUGUCGUGUUCAGAGGCUGCGGGAGUGGGCGGUGGACGUGGGCUCCCACAAACAUGGUGAGCGCUGGACAGGCCCCGUGUGAACACUCACUGUUGAGGGGCCCCCAGGCCCCGUGUGAACACUCACUGUUGAGGGGUCCCUGGGCCCCCAGGCACCGUGUGAGCAUUCACUGUUGAGGGUCCCCCAGUCCCCCAGGCCAGGGGCUGUCCCUGGAGCCCUCAGGAGGCAGUAAGAAACAUCUAGAAGAGGGCAGACCCAGUGGUGAACCGCAUCCAACAGUGGUGAGAUGGGUGCAGCUCUACAGGGGCGUAAUUUACAAACCACCAGACUCCCUGGUUAUGUGUGUGCUGCGGUGGUGUUUGCUCUCCAGCAGAUCAAGUUUGUGCAAUGAUCCAUUUUGAGAAUCUCUCCGUCACCCCAAGAAGUCCUCUCGCACCCAUCAGUCCGACCCCUUCCCCGUGCUCCUCCCCAGCCCUGGCAGCCACUCACCUGCACUCCAGACGCUCCAGAUGUCAUGCAUGUCUCCUGGCUUCCUUCGGCUGUUUUCACGCGCCAUCCUCACGGCAGGCUGUAUCAGGACUUCAUUCCAUUUCAUGGCUGAAGCACAUUCCAUUGCAUGCAGGGACCACAUUUUGUUUGUCUGCUCUUCUGUCCAUGGACAUCUGGGUUGCUUCCAGUUUGGGGCUUCUGUGAAUCCUGCUGCUGUGGACAUUUGCGUAGUCCUCGUGUGGAUGCUGCUGUGGACGUCUGCGUCGUCCUCGUGUGGAUGCUGCUGUGGACGUCUGCGUCGUCCUCGUGUGGAUGCUGCUGUGGACGUCUGCGUAGUCUCGUGUGGAUGCUGCUGUGGACGUCUGCGUCGUCCUCGUGUGGAUGCUGCUGUGGACAUCUGCGUAGUCUCGUGUGGAUGCUGCUGUGAACGUCUGCGUAGUCUCGUGUGGAUGCUGCUGUGGACGUCUGCGUAGUCUCGUGUGGAUGCUGCUGUGCACGUCUGCGUCGUCCUCGUGUGGAUGCUGCUGUGGACGUCUGCGUCGUCCUCGUGUGGAUGCUGCUGUGGACGUCUGCGUCGUCCUCGUGUGGAUGCUGCUGUGGACGUCUGCGUCGUCUCGUGUGGAUGCUGCUGUGGACGUCUGCGUCGUCUCGUGUGGAUGCUGCUGUGGACGUCUGCGUCGUCUCGUGUGGAUGCUGCUGUGGACGUCUGCGUCGUCCUCGUGUGGAUGCUGCUGUGGACGUCUGCGUCGUCUCGUGUGGAUGCUGCUGUGGACGUCUGCGUCGUCCUCGUGUGGAUGCUGCUGUGGACGUCUGCGUCGUCCUCGUGUGGAUGCUGCUGUGGACGUCUGCGUCGUCCUCGUGUGGAUGCUGCUGUGGACGUCUGCGUCGUCCUCCUGUGGAUGCUGCUGUGGACGUCUGCGUCGUCCUCGUGUGGAUGCUGCUGUGGACGUCUGCGUAGUCUCGUGUGGAUGCUGCUGUGGACGUCUGCGUAGUCUCGUGUGGAUGCUGCUGUGGACGUCUGCGUCGUCCUCGAUGCUGCUGUGGACGUCUGCGUCGUCCUCGUGUGGAUGCUGCUAUGGACGUCUGCGUAGUCUCGUGUGGAUGCUGCUGUGGACGUCUGCGUCGUCCUCGUGUGGAUGCUGCUGUGGACGUCUGCGUAGUCUCGUGUGGAUGCUGCUGUGGACGUCUGCGUAGUCUCGUGUGGAUGCUGCUGUGGACGUCUGCGUCGUCCUCGUGUGGAUGCUGCUGUGGACGUCUGCGUAGUCUCGUGUGGAUGCUGCUGUGGACGUCUGCGUCGUCCUCGUGUGGAUGCUGCUGUGGACGUCUGUGUAGUCUCAUGUGGAUGCUGCGAGUUUUCGUUGCUCUGGGGUAGAUUCGUAGCGGAGGAACAACUGGGCGACACGCUAAGUUUAUGUUUAACUUUUUAAGUAACUGCCUAACUGUUUUCCAAAGCAGCUGCACCAUUUUUCAUUCCCAUCCAUGCUAUUGUUUUUCAGUUAAAUAGCUCCACUCCUCCCCCUCCCCACCCUCCACAGAACUGCCAGUAAAACUGGACUAUGGAGUAUUGGGUGGGGUCACCUACAAGGUCAUCUGCAGCAAGUGAGACCAUCGCCCCUCCUGCCUGGAGAGGUGGGACUGGGGACCCUGUGACAGGAGGAGCUGCCCUUCCUGGAGCCUGGUUUUUCUUUUUCCUCUGUGCUCCAUGAGAAGUCAGUUUAGUGGGCUACAGCCAGCAAAGGAACCAAAACCAACAGGAGCUCUGGGGGUGCCUUGCAUGGCGAGGCUCCGUGGCUGCACGCGUGUAUGCAGGUGGCUGUGGGUGUCUGUGUGUCCUGGGCCACUGUGUGCGAUGGUCCCACUGGGAGGUGUGGCCCCCAAAGAGUGGAACCCACAGGUGGACACACCCAUGCACCCUCGUUCUUGCCCAAGGUCACACAUCGAGACAGCAGGGCCCAGAUGGAUGGCCCCAAGCUCGGUGGCUCCCGUGCUGCCCACACCUGGGGACAGGCCCACUGUGGGGGGUAAGGGGUGGAGGUGUUCUAAUUCGGGCUGAGCCGUGUGACUGGCAGGGGCCCCAGCUGUUGGGCCUGGGCAGGACUGUUUUUAGAAAAGCCCCAACUCCCUGCCCCUACCCGGGCCCGUGGCUAUUUAUAGUCCGGGCCUGGAGAAGUCAGUGAGUCACUAGCGUUCGCCUCUGCAGGGUCAGUCCAAGCCCCCUUAGUGAGGUGGUCUAGCAUGUCCCCCAGUCCCCCAAGCCUCUAUCUGACAUCUGCUAGCCCAGAGCCCCAGGGGUCCCCAGGAAGGGCUCAGAGCUGGUGGCCCCCCCCAGGCCUUGGCAGCACCUCCUUGUCUGAUGGGACUUUGUGGUUCCUGGUGGACAUUUAACAUUGUCGGUUUCUCUCAUCUGGAAACAAACCUCCAUGACGCUC